GGAAGGGGCGGGCCCGCCGGGAGCCAGGCCGCUCGGCGCCACGACCGGCCGAGAGGGGGGCCGGAUCCCGGACCAUGGCGGCGGCGGGGGGCGCCGAGGGGCGGCGCGCGGACAUGGAGGCGGAGGCGGCGGCAGCUCCUGAGCGGGGAGGCGGGAGCUGCGUGCUGUGCUGCGGAGACCUGGAGGCCACGGCGCUGGGCCGCUGCGACCACCCGGUGUGCUACCGCUGCUCUACCAAGAUGCGGGUGCUCUGCGAGCAGCGCUACUGCGCCGUGUGCCGCGAGGAGCUGCGCCAGGUGGUCUUUGGGAAGAAGCUUCCUGCCUUUGCCACCAUCCCCAUCCACCAGCUGCAGCAUGAGAAGAAAUAUGAUAUCUACUUUGCAGAUGGAAAGGUGUACGCAUUGUACAGGCAGCUGCUGCAGCACGAGUGCCCGCGGUGCCCCGAGCUGCCACCUUUCAGCCUCUUCGGGGACCUGGAGCAGCACAUGCGGAGGCAGCAUGAGCUCUUCUGCUGCCGUCUGUGCCUCCAGCACCUCCAGAUCUUCACAUAUGAGCGCAAGUGGUACUCGCGCAAGGACCUGGCCCGGCAUCGCAUGCAGGGUGACCCCGAUGACACGUCGCACCGUGGGCACCCGCUCUGCAAGUUCUGUGACGAGCGCUACCUGGACAAUGAUGAGCUGCUUAAGCACCUGCGCCGCGACCACUACUUCUGCCACUUCUGCGACUCGGACGGGGCCCAGGACUACUACAGCCCUCCUACCGACACCCCAUCUCCUGCCAGCGACUAUGCCUACCUGCGUGAGCACUUCCGGGAGAAGCACUUUCUGUGUGAGGAAGGCCGCUGCAGCACGGAGCAGUUCACCCACGCCUUCCGCACCGAGAUCGACCUCAAGGCCCACAGGACGGCCUGCCACAGUCGCAGCCGCGCCGAGGCACGCCAGAACCGCCACAUCGACCUGCAGUUCAGCUACGCGCCACGGCACUCGCGCCGGAACGAGGGGGUCGUUGGUGGCGAAGACUACGAGGAGGUGGACAGGUACAGCCGCCAGGGCCGAGUGGCCCGGGCUGGCACUCGCGGAGCCCAGCAGAGCCGCCGAGGAAGCUGGAGGUACAAAAGGGAAGAAGAGGACCGAGAAGUAGCAGCUGCUGUCCGGGCCUCCGUGGCCGCACAGCAGCAGGAGGAGGCUCGCAGGAGUGAGGAUCAGGAGGAAGGCGGUAGGCCCAAGAAGGAGGAGGCAGCGGCGCGGGGACCUGAGGAUCCCCGUGGCCCCCGGCGCUCACCCCGGACUCAGGGCGAAGGCCCAGGCCCCAAGGAAACCUCGACAAAUGGUCCUGUAAGCCAAGAAGCCUUCUCGGUGACAGGCCCAGCCGCCCCAGGGUGUGUGGGGGUGCCAGGCGCCCUCCCACCACCCAGCCCGAAGCUCAAGGACGAAGACUUCCCCAGCCUCUCUGCCUCCACUUCCUCCUCCUGCUCCACUGCAGCAACCCCGGGCCCUGUGGGGUUGGCGCUGCCGUACGCCAUCCCUGCCAGAGGCAGGAGUGCCUUCCAGGAGGAGGACUUCCCCGCCCUGGUGUCCUCGGUGCCCAAGCCUGGCACCGCCCCCACCAGCCUUGUCUCUGCCUGGAACAGCAGCAGUAGCAGCAAGAAGGUAGCACAGCCCCCACUCUCGGCGCAGGCUACCGGCAGCGGCCAGCCCACCAGGAAGGCUGGGAAGGGGAGCAGGGGCGGCAGGAAGGGCGGCCCGCCCUUCACACAGGAGGAGGAGGAGGACGGCGGCCCGGCCCUGCAGGAGCUUCUGAGCACACGCCCCACGGGCUCCGUCUCCUCCACACUGGGGCUGGCCUCCAUCCAACCCUCUAAAGUUGGGAAGAAGAAGAAAGUGGGCUCGGAGAAGCCAGGCACCACAUUGCCACAGCCCCCGCCCGCUACCUGUCCCCCAGGGGCUUUGCAGGCCCCGGAAGCUCCUGCCAGCAGAGCCGAGGGGCCAGUUGCCGUCGUCGUUAAUGGACACAUGGAGGGCCCGGCCCCUGCUCGGAGUGCCCCCAAGGAACCCCCUGGGCUCCCAAGGCCCCUGGGGUCCUUCCCCUGCCCCACGCCACAGGAGGACUUCCCAGCGCUCGGCGGCCCCUGCCCACCCCGGAUGCCGCCGCCCCCAGGCUUCAGCGCUGUGGUGCUCCUGAAGGGCACGCCUCCCCCACCCCCGCCGGGCCUGGUGCCCCCAAUCAGCAAGCCGCCCCCUGGCUUCUCUGGCCUUCUGCCUAGCCCCCACCCGGCCUGUGUCCCCAGCCCCGCCACCACCACCACCACAAAAGCACCCAGGCUGCUGCCUGCCCCACGGGCGUACCUAGUCCCCGAGAACUUCCGGGAGAGGAACCUUCAGCUCAUCCAGUCCAUCAGGGACUUCCUGCAGAGCGACGAGGCCCGCUUCAGCGAGUUCAAGAGCCACUCAGGGGAGUUCAGACAGGGCCUGAUCUCCGCAGCCCAGUAUUACAAGAGUUGCCGGGACCUGCUGGGGGAGAAUUUCCAGAAGGUCUUUAAUGAGCUGCUGGUCCUGCUGCCCGACACGGCCAAGCAGCAGGAGCUCCUGUCUGCACACACGGACUUCUGCAACCGCGAGAAGCCUCUGAGCACCAAGUCCAAGAAGAACAAGAAGAGCGCGUGGCAGGCCACCACCCAGCAGGCGGGCCUGGACUGCCGUGUGUGCCCCACCUGCCAGCAGGUGCUCGCGCAUGGCGAUGCCAGCAGCCACCAGGCGCUGCAUGCUGCCCGGGACGACGACUUCCCCUCCCUGCAAGCCAUCGCCAGGAUCAUCACGUAGCUCCCGCCAGCGUGGCCAGAGCUGUCGCACCGUGAGCGUCCUUCCUCCUUCCUCUCCGGGCUGCCAGGCAGCCAGGUAAGGCCUGGUGAGGCCACUUGGCCUCUUGGUUGGCCAGGCCCACCAGGAAGUCACCAGGACAGUCCACCCGCCCUGUUGGCACACUCAAGCGGGAGUCCACCCCUGCCUCAGUGGUGGGCCAGUCUCGGUUUGCAUUCUUGUGCUUUUGGGAGGUGCCAGGGGAGGGAAGGGCUGGGAUGCUGGGACCUGUUGUUGCUGGCAAAGCCAGAGGUCACAGUGGCCUGAUCUGGGCCCUCCCAAAGCUGAGGGCUGCAGCCCGUGGGGCCUCAGAGCUGAAAGCUGCGGCGCCACUGGUGCCAGAGUCAGAUGUCACAGAUGUGUUGUGUAAACAGUUGGCUGUUUCAUGCUUCAAGAAUGUUCAGGAUUAAAAGCAGACAAGAAAUUGUGCUACUUGAAGUUGAAUCUUUUUAUGAGACAAGCUGAAUCUGGGAUCUCAAAUUGCCUCUGACCUUUUAUAAGACAGUUUAUCUUCAAAUAAAUUUAUUUUGCAAUACCACGCA